GCAGAACACUGCGUGUCCUGUGCGCGAGUACGGGUCCGGCCGCGGGUCCCACCGCAAGCGGGCGUGUGCAGCUGCGGCUGCCUGGCGGGCGAGCUUAGGAGGGAGCUGGAGCUGCGGAGCGGCGGGAACAGGAGCAGGCCGAGGGUCCUCUGGCCAGAAGAAAUCUGGCCUCGGAACACGCCAUUCUCCGCGCCGCUUCCAAUAACCACUAACAUCCCUAACGAGCAUCCGAGCCGAGGGCUCUGCUCGGAAAUCGUCCUGGCCCAACUCGGCCCUUCGAGCUCUCGAAGAUUACCGCAUCUAUUUUUUUUUCUUUUUUUUCUUUUCCUAGCGCAGAUAAAGUGAGCCCGGAAAGGGAAGGAGGGGGCGGGGACACCAUUGCCCUGAAAGAAUAAAUAAGUAAAUAAACAAACUGGCUCCUCGCCGCAGCUGGACGCGGUCGGUUGAGUCCAGGUUGGGUCGGACCUGAACCCCUAAAAGCGGAACCGCCUCCCGCCCUCGCCAUCCCGGAGCUGAGUCGCCGGCGGCGGUGGCUGCUGCCAGACCCGGAGUUUCCUCUUUCACUGGAUGGAGCUGAACUUUGGGCGGCCAGAGCAGCACAGCUGUCCGGGGAUCGCUGCACGCUGAGCUCCCUCGGCAAGACCCAGCGGCGGCUCGGGAUUUUUUUGGGGGGGCGGGGACCAGCCCCGCGCCGGCACCAUGUUCCUGGCGACCCUGUACUUCGCGCUGCCGCUCUUGGACUUGCUCCUGUCGGCCGAAGUGAGCGGCGGAGACCGCCUGGAUUGCGUGAAAGCCAGUGAUCAGUGCCUGAAGGAGCAGAGCUGCAGCACCAAGUACCGCACGCUAAGGCAGUGCGUGGCGGGCAAGGAGACCAACUUCAGCCUGGCAUCCGGCCUGGAGGCCAAGGAUGAGUGCCGCAGCGCCAUGGAGGCCCUGAAGCAGAAGUCGCUCUACAACUGCCGCUGCAAGCGGGGUAUGAAGAAGGAGAAGAACUGCCUGCGCAUUUACUGGAGCAUGUACCAGAGCCUGCAGGGAAAUGAUCUGCUGGAGGAUUCCCCAUAUGAACCAGUUAACAGCAGAUUGUCAGAUAUAUUCCGGGUGGUCCCAUUCAUAUCAGUGGAGCACAUUCCCAAAGGGAACAACUGCCUGGAUGCAGCGAAGGCCUGCAACCUCGACGACAUUUGCAAGAAGUACAGGUCGGCGUACAUCACCCCGUGCACCACCAGCGUGUCCAACGAUGUCUGCAACCGCCGCAAGUGCCACAAGGCCCUCCGGCAGUUCUUUGACAAGGUCCCGGCCAAGCACAGCUACGGAAUGCUCUUCUGCUCCUGCCGGGACAUCGCCUGCACAGAGCGGAGGCGACAGACCAUCGUGCCUGUGUGCUCCUAUGAAGAGAGGGAGAAGCCCAACUGUUUGAAUUUGCAGGACUCCUGCAAGACGAAUUACAUCUGCAGAUCUCGCCUUGCGGAUUUUUUUACCAACUGCCAGCCAGAGUCAAGGUCUGUCAGCAGCUGUCUAAAGGAAAACUACGCUGACUGCCUCCUCGCCUACUCGGGGCUUAUUGGCACAGUCAUGACCCCCAACUACAUAGACUCCAGUAGCCUCAGUGUGGCCCCAUGGUGUGACUGCAGCAACAGUGGGAACGACCUAGAAGAGUGCUUGAAAUUUUUGAAUUUCUUCAAGGACAAUACAUGUCUUAAAAAUGCAAUUCAAGCCUUUGGCAAUGGCUCCGAUGUGACCGUGUGGCAGCCAGCCUUCCCAGUACAGACCACCACUGCCACUACCACCACUGCCCUCCGGGUUAAGAACAAGCCCCUGGGGCCAGCAGGGUCUGAGAAUGAAAUUCCCACUCAUGUUUUGCCACCGUGUGCAAAUUUACAGGCACAGAAGCUGAAAUCCAAUGUGUCGGGCAAUACACACCUCUGUAUUUCCAAUGGUAAUUAUGAAAAAGAAGGUCUCGGUGCUUCCAGCCACAUAACCACAAAAUCAAUGGCUGCUCCUCCAAGCUGUGGUCUGAGCCCACUGCUGGUCCUGGUGGUAACCGCUCUGUCCACCCUAUUAUCUUUAACAGAAACAUCAUAGCUGCAUUAAAAAAAUACAAUAUGGACAUGUAAAAAGACAAAAACCAAGUUAUCUGUUUCCUGUUCUCUUGUAUAGCUGAAAUUCCAGUUUAGGAGCUCAGUUGAGAAACAGUUCCAUUCAACUGGAACAUUUUUUUUUUUUCCUUUUAAGAAAGCUUCUUGUGAUCCUUUGGGGCUUCUGUGAAAAACCUGAUGCAGUGCUCCAUCCAAACUCAGAAGGCUUUGGGAUAUGCUGUAUUUUAAAGGGACAGUUUGUAACUUGGGCUGUAAAGCAAACUGGGGCUGUGUUUUCGAUGAUGAUGAUGAUCAUGAUGAUGAUCAUCAUGAUCAUGAUGAUGAUCAUCAUGAUCAUGAUGAUGAUUUUAACAGUUUUACUUCUGGCCUUUCCUAGCUAGAGAAGGAGUUAAUAUUUCUAAGGUAACUCCCAUAUCUCCUUUAAUGACAUUGAUUUCUAAUGAUAUAAAUUUCAGCCUACAUUGAUGCCAAGCUUUUUUGCCACAAAGAAGAUUCUUACCAAGAGUGGGCUUUGUGGAAACAGCUGGUACUGAUGUUCACCUUUAUAUAUGUACUAGCAUUUUCCACGCUGAUGUUUAUGUACUGUAAACAGUUCUGCACUCUUGUACAAAAGAAAAAACACCUGUCACAUCCAAAUAUAGUAUCUGUCUUUUCGUCAAAAUAGAGAGUGGGGAAUGAGUGUGCCGAUUCAAUACCUCAAUCCCUGAACGACACUCUCCUAAUCCUAAGCCUUACCUGAGUGAGAAGCCCUUUACCUAACAAAAGUCCAAUAUAGCUGAAAUGUCGCUCUAAUACUCUUUACACAUAUGAGGUUAUAUGUAGAAAAAAAUUUUACUACUAAAUGAUUUCAACUAUUGGCUUUCUAUAUUUUGAAAGUAAUGAUAUUGUCUCAUUUUUUUACUGAUGGUUUAAUACAAAAUACACAGAGCUUCUUUCCCCUCAUAAGUAGUGUUCGCUCUGAUAUGAACUUCACAAAUACAGCUCAUCAAAAGCAGACUCUGAGAAGCCUCGUGCUGUAGCAGAAAGUUCUGCAUCAUGUGACUGUGGACAGGCAGGAGGAAACAGAACAGACAAGCAUUGUCUUUUGUCAUUGCUCGAAGUGCAAGCGUGCAUACCUGUGGAGGGAACUGGUGGCUGCUUGUAAAUGUUCUGCAGCAUCUCUUGACACACUUGUCAUGACACAAUCCAGUACCUUGGUUUUCAGGUUAUCUGACAAAGGCAGCUUUGAUUGGGACAUGGAGGCAUGGGCAGGUUCUCCUUUCUUUGGAAACACAUCCAUGCUGGGAUGCACAGUUCUUUUCCUAAGGAUUGUGUUUACUCCUGACUGCAACGUCUUGGCCACUGUUUGGAGCAGUUUGGUCUGAAGGUCAUUAAGGAUCUGCUUGCAUCUUGUUUCAUGUCCUCCGUGACAGACUGCAGACCAUGUUAGAAGAGAAGGAAGGUUUGUGGAUCAAGAGGGUUGACAUUAGGUUUGGUGAGAUGAGUUGCUUGGCACAGAUCAGCAGAACAGGACCCUGGUGAUAAGGCAUCUGGCUUUGCUAACCACUUAUCAUCUUCCAUUAUUCUCUUUCUUAACUAAGUAGACCCGAAAGUGCACUUUUGAAGUCUGGUUUAGAUGGCGAGAUUCCGAAUCUACAAUGAUCGAGUACUGGUGGCCACUUUUCUCCAACAUUAAGUAAAGAGGAGGAGAUUCCACCUUCAGAAAGUGCUGGGAAGCAUUGGCUUUCUUCCCACAUUGGUAGAAGAGAUGGAGGAGGAAACCAGGGUGCACAUUUCUACAGAUCCCCUUUGCCUGCUGGUGUUUGCCUUGUAAGAUAAGUCACUGGGGGGAAGGGGAAAUCUAUGAAAUCCAAGAUAAAGGCAUAGUCUUUCAGCUCUAUUGGUGUUAAAAGUAUAUUUGUGUCCAAAUGUUAAUCAACACAAAUGUACAGUACUCAGUACUGACUUUUUUCACUUCAAAAUGUUUUCAAGGGAAAUUCAGCAGACACCCAACUGUAUUUAAUUAGUGAAAAGAUCUAUAAAGACUCUUACUUUGAAUAAACACAUUAAGUAAGUGUGUCAAAAUAUUUGGAAUGCCAGUUAUCUAUGAGCGCAUAUCUCUUACAGAGUGUAUUUUGUUUUCAUUAAGGUAUCUCUGUGUAUCUACACUGGACUAAUUUCAUAGGGAUCUGAUUCUAUGUGAUCCACUGUAGAAAGCUACUGAUUACUUCUGCAGUAACAGCAGCUCUAAUUAGCAUCAGAUGACCAAAGCGGAAAUGGGAGUUUCAGCGCUAACAAGGGCAGCCUUCAUUGAAGAAUGCAUGGGUAGGCAAUAUAUAAAUUACAUUUUGAAAAGCCUCAUCUGUCACCAACAAAUAUCUCAUUUUUCUUCAGUGAUAAAAGCAUAUUCAAGUUACCAGCUCCUCAAUUUGAAAAUCAGUUGCUGAUUAAAUAAAUAGGGGGAAGCAUCUUGUUCAGGGACAACACGUUAGAGAGAUUCUUAUCAAAGCAAGCCAAGCAAGGUUUCCGCCAUUCAGUGUGAUCUUAGUUUGACACGGUGACCCUAAAACACCAUCAUUUGCCCCAGAACUGGAGCACAAUAAGUUAAAUCAUUUACCUGUCUCACUUCUUCUUGGCGUGCUUAAAAGCAAAAAUGAUUCGCUACUUCCUGUCCUUCAGUCCGGGCAUUUGGGGUGCCACUGAAGACAGGGGUUAUCUGCUGAGGUUUGGGUGUCUUGCAGGAAGUAUCUCAUUGCAGUUGAUUUUGAUGAAACCAAACAGUAACUAGGGUCCAUGCAGACCGUGACUCCCUGAUUACAUCUAGCCAUGCCCUACUUAUUUCAGAGAGAAAGAGAGGGGGAAUAAAGGCAGUAUUGCCACACUGAUUAGAAGCACAUUCAUUCCACUUUGAUGUUGAAUAUUUUUGACCGAUACAUGCUUGAGUAUCUUUUUAAUAGAGCACAUGAAGGAAGAAGCACACAAUAUAGAGAAGGAAUUGAGAAUGCCAAUUACAUAUUUAUUUUUCCAUACCUGAUUUUUUUCAAGUCUGUAAUAAAAAAAGUAUAAGUUGAGAUUAACAUAGGUUAUUUUUCAUGAAGUAUAGCAAACGAUCUAGAAUGUGAUAGGAGUGUGGUUUCCAUUUCUUUUUUUUUUUUUUUAACAGACUUUUGUGCUGUAGUAAGAAUGUCUUAGAAGUUGUGUCUUCGAGUUCCUCAAACACCGGACAGGGCUCCCCCAGAGCUGCCUCAGCCUUUGAUUUGGUCCAUAUUCAGACACUUCCUGUCUUGCAUACACUCUGAGGAUGGGCCGCUUCUAGCUGCCGCCCGUCUCCCUCUUGCCUUCUUGUCUCUAAAUCAGACACUCCCAAGCACUCCAUCUGCUAUACUAGGAGAGUGGGAGAGCCAAAGCAUUUUGGAGUCCAUGUAAAGUGCCUGGGAAAAGAGAUGUAAGAGCAGUGGGAGUUUAUAUAAUUAGCGAAUUCUUUUCUCAGAAUUCAGCGGAAAUGUAUUUCUGUUGUUAUUAUUUACAAAAUUGUGGCCUCAGAGGAGCUGUCUUUUGGAAAAUAAGUUUUCAUUCAUGCAGUUAGUUAGACAUGCACGAUGUACUUGAAUCAAUAAACUGUGGACCAGAAAAGGGCUGCUUAAAUGAAUUCACGUGUUCUAAUUCUCUUUCGAGGCUGUUGAUGACCUCCUGGAUUCAUACCCCCAUGAUCUGUCUUGCUCUUGCCUCUGUUCUUUGAUAAAGCACAUCAGACUAUGUGACACCCAUCUUUUCAAGAACGACCUAAAAGCAAUGACAACAGGCAGGAGAGAAUUACCACUGGCCUGGGCACAGUGACAGCAGAAGGCCCACCUGAGCUUGGAGAGUUGGCGAGAUAAGGCAAAAUCAAGGUGCAACAGUGGGCCAUGUUCCAAGGGUGAAUGGAUCUGAGAGUCCGCUGAUGUUCCUUACUGAUCAGAACAGGGACCUUCUAACGAAACAGCCAGAGUUCCUUGAAUCAGGCAGAAGUUCUUUAGAGACAGGAAGCCAGAGCUAUUGAUAAUAUCCGAACGACAGAGGAAGGAAUUUCUUAUUAGAAAUUCUAAAAUAAAACAAGUGGGGAUUUGGUUGGAUACCCUUAGAAGCUACAUUUUUCUCUCAUCCCUAAGAUAGAUAUCUCAAGUGUAUAUCUGACACCUCUUGGCUUUGACACGGCUCUGCUUCUCAAGUGACCAUUUGUUUUAAGUCUGUUGUCUAGAAUUCUUUGUGGGGGCUGGACCUCUGAAAAAGAUUCUCACUGCAGAGGCUUUAAAUCUGUGUUUUUUUCCACUCCCUCCGUCCUGGGAUGUAUUCGGUAGGACAUUUCAUUUAUAUCAGGAUAUUGGCUGAUUCAGCUCUCUUUCAUCGUUAUUAUUCAGGCCUCCCUCCACCACCUUGUUCUUUAUUGCCUAAGUAUUGCCCUCCCCAAUUCUUCAUCGUAAUAGCUCUAAAUUUAGUUUGACCCAAAUUAAUUUUUGUUCCAACAGAUAUAUUUUAAGACAGAGAAGCCUCUCUCAGGAGCCAGAUGAUCUGAAGAUGAUGCUAAUCCCCAAAUACGAAGUUCCUCCAGCUAACUCUCCUCUGAGCUCCCUCUUCUUAGCUUUGGGAUUGGGGAUGGUCUCAUCCUUGCCAGGAAUCCCUUUGUUGCUCCCAGUGUCUCUGAUGAGCUUCUCCUCCCUCCCAGAGACAAUGCAGGGGUGGUUUUCAGCAGAAUGUGCCACCUGCACUUCUGAUUGUUCUGAGACCCAGCCCAGAGGGGUGGAGAAGGCGCACAAACCCUAUUCCAAUAAACUGCCUGCAGAGAACCACAGCCUGCUAAUAGUCGUUGAGGUCUCAGCCCCCUAAGGUCUCCAAGCUCAUUUGACCAGCGCAGCUGCGACUUCGGCUGUCUGCCUCUGGCAGGUGCCAAUAUCAGCAUCUUGUCCCACUGCCAUGGGGAGUUAAUUUUUGCUCCAGGGCAGCUGCCAAGCCCAGCACCGGCAUCAAUAGAAGGUUUUCUCUGAUUUUCUUCUCUUCCUCUCAGGCUAGGCUUUCUUACCAAUCCCCAAUUUUCUUCUGUAGGGCGCCAGGAGACUGGCCAGAGAUCUUUAGACUCUUACUUAGUUUGAACAUCUCUUGCUGCUCACACCCAGGCUUCUUCAGCAGAAAGCAUGACCCAUAGUAGGUACUCAGAAACUGGUUGAAUGAAAAGCCUUGACAUUUAAGGGCUUUAUUCUGUCAUACGGUAGCAAGAACUGGCCUAUUGGCAUCGUAUUCCUGGCAUUGAGCUGUAUUGACCCUGAAUGUGUCCUCCUGAGGUUUUUGAGGGUGACCUAGGAGAAAGGGUCUGAAAAAGCACUGGGAUCCAAGUGACUUUAAAUCUGCCCGUGGCAUUUCCUGCUGAGAGGCGAGAAACUAGCAUCUCUCCCAACAGGCUCACAUCCGCCAGGAAGGACAGAGCCCAAAACGGGGGUAGACUUUGUGGGAAAUUCGCCAGUUAGUCCGCUGAGAUUUUAAUCUGCCUCAAGCACAGGAUGCUGACAAGAAAGGUAGACCACUCCCCCGAUCCCAGACAAACCCCAGGGGUGACAACUUCUCCAUCAGUAUCCUGAGAAGCAACAUCAAAUGCUUACCAAGUCAGCACGUUUACUGAGUGAGUACUCUGACGGAAUAAACCAGCAUUUGGAGCUGAACUUGAGAACACAGGGCCCUCUGACAGCAGCUUAGGGAAACACCCAUCCCUUCCAGAUUGGCAGAAUCCUUCCAUUUCAUGUCCUUCGGAGACGCUGUAUUCUCUUUACAAAUCAUUCAUGAAACUGAGACUCAGUCUCCCAGGGGUAAGUCCUGGGCCACGUGCAAACAAUGGCAAAUCCAGCUCUUCCAUGAUAGAGAAGGCAAACACACCCACCUUCAUCCUGAGCCUAAAAGGCCACCUCUGAGCACUUGGGCAGCCACUCCUCUGGGCCUCAGAGGGCCAUGAGCUUGGCCAGGUAGGCACAGCGGCGGGGAAGUCACAGCUGUCAGGUACCGGCCAUGGUGCAGGUGGGAAUAGGAGAUGCCAGAGCUGCUUUAGCUGAGGAAAGCAAACAGUCAGCAGUGCUCAAAGGAGCAAAACUUCGAAUGUGCACAUUGACCCCUGACACCUGCAAGCAUAACACAGAUCCUAAGACUAGAGUGAAGUAGGAAGAAGAAUUAGAAAAUCCAGUGGAUGUCCUGAGUAUAGGGAACCAGGGCCGUUGAAAAUCAGUAAAGGUUGAUUACCUGGGGCGAGACCGGGUGACUGUGGCAGUGCAGGUGAAGGUACCCUGGACCUUCUCAGUUCGCUGGCACAUAAGGCUCCGCCAAUAAAGCGUGGUUCUCUCUGUCACACACACACACACACACACACACACACACACACACACACACACACACACAAUGAUUGGAGGGCUAUAUGAUCCAGCAUUAGCUUCCUGGUGUGCCAAGCAUGCUUGAUCGGGAAUUUUUUUUUAUUAUUAUUAUUUUUUAGCUGUAGCUGAAGGCAUUUCUCGGAUGUGGAGAGGAGAAUGGAAAUCGCAGAACCAAAUCAGUUUGCCCUGCCAUAUUUGGCUGUGGUCUGUCAUUGGGCAUUUCUGAUGUGCUUUUCUGGAUUCAGGAAGAGCUGAUUGUCCUCCGAGGGUUGAAAAAAAAAAAACAGUUUCAGAAACCUGAAUCCAGGGCCUUAUAGUUCUCCUCAUUAUCUAUCUUCUUCUCCCUUCCCUCGCCCAAGGGAGUGGGGGAAACACUUUUCACUGCAGAGUUUGCUUUAAAGUUUUCCCAUCUUGCGUGCAUUAUCCCUUGAUAUUAAAAUUAUUUUCUCAGUUUAAUCCAACUCCUGCUGAGAAGCUGUGUGAGAUUUAGGCUGUGGGGUUUUUUUCUUGUACUCUUUUGGAUGGUGUUGCAUUUUUCACUCUUAACCCGAGGGUGUGUUUCAGCUUAUGUUCGUUCUGUUUCAUGCAGGUUUAUAGCACGGUAGAGUAGAAGGCGGCUUCUGAUUUUUAGGGUAUUUUUAGAAUUCAUUCCUGAGUGAGGGGUUCAGACACCCAGUCUCCUCGGAACAGGGGUGAGGGGUCGACUGAGCUUUGUUGAGAAGCCUCCAGUUAGGCUUCGGGCGGGUCUCCAUGUUAUAUUGUGUGUUUACUGAGCUUCCCACUGGUAGAAGAUGACACAUUUGUCCAUCGUCCUGUGUAUCUGCUUUCCAGAGGACACCGGAGCAUUCUCCUGGGGUCACUCCCACAUGGCUGCCUCACAUAGCUGUUUUGCAACAGCCUUUAUUGCCAACACCCUUGGAAGAACAUCUCCUGUAGAAGUACAAGUUUUGCAAUAUGGACUUUGGAAGUGGUUUUGUGAUGUUCGAAUUUUCUGUUAGCCUAUUGCUCAAGCACUACAGAAUGUACAUAGUCCCUUUGGCCAUCCUCUCACCCCAGAAUAUCCUAAUAAACAUUGUUUUCUUUUUUAAAAAAAA